GUUUCCGGGGUGGAGCCAGGGAGGGCGGGAGUUUAGGCUGCGCUGACCCCUCUCAGCCCCCCCUCCAGGUGACCCCAGCCCCUGAAAAUCCUCACCCAGGGCCCCAAAUCUCCCAGCCCCAUGACCGCCAAACCUCUCGCCCUGGCCCCCUAAAUGCCCCAGGCCCCGGAGAUGACCGGCCUCCUCACCCCUUAACUUCCAGUGCCUCCCAAAUCUCCAAGCCCACCCUGUCCCGUGGUGGCAACUGAGGCUUCUCGGGGGCAUCAGCCUCAGAUUACCUGAGAACUGGGCAGCCUCGUCCUGAGAAUGACGGAGAAGGGGACCUGGGGCUAGGGAAUCCCUGAUUCAAUCAUGCCGCUCCCCAGGAGACGUUCGGAGCCCAGGACAUGUCGGGAAUGAGGAGAUACGAGGUGGCGCUGGAGGCGGAGGAGGAGAUCUACUGGGGCUGUUUCUACUUUUUCCCCUGGCUUCGCAUGUGGCGGAGGGAGCGGAGCUCGGCGCACCCCGGGGAGCAGAAGCUGGAGCCUCUGCGAGGCCUGAUGAGCUGUCUGUCCAGCGGCCUGGGUCCUACUCCCCAGCGCUCGGGUCGUGGCUUCCCCCGCCGCAGCCCCACCGCCGCUGCCCAGCCAGCCAGUGCAUUAAAGAUUUAAACCGAAGCCCACCGUACUGACCUCCUGACUCUGCCGCCGCUGUCGCCAUUCGAGCCGAGCGCCCCUCCCCACACGGGCUCUGUUCCGUACUGACAGGGCGUCCCUCCCUGGAAGGGUGCCCUUCCACGUCAAAGCCCCUCAUCAGUGUCAGGCCUCCUGUUACUAUCAAUGGCUGUCUCCCCCAAUCCCAACCCCCAAAAACCCAUACUGUGAGUCGCCUAUAUGAAGAGAACUAAAUAAUCCUGCCUGUUACUCCCUUCCUCGGAGCGAGGACUUUGCCAGCUGUCUGAAGAAUCUUCUCUGCUGGGAGUAUAUCUAAAACAUUUUAAGCAGAGGUGUAGGAUGCAGGCUGUAAAUGGUAAGAGGGGGAGAUUCCUAGAAGCUGCCUGCCACAGAGGAGCGACUUGGGUUGGCGACCUUUCCUACAGUUCAUACCCCAACUUUUGGCUCCUCCAGUCUGAUCCCAAGUUUAGAGAUCCUUGGCAUCAGCCUACCUAGAAGUUCUUGCUCCCUCCCUAGGAGAGUCCAAGGGCCACUGCUCUUUGCCGCCCCCUUCUGUCACCCAAUCAGCCUGGGACCCACUAACUCCUCAAGUGGUGAGAAUCAGGGACUGCUAUGUGGGCCUGCCUUCAGUUAGGGACUGGACCCAGCACCAGAAAGGGCACCACAAGAUUAAGUUAAAGAAAGAGAUGGCCCAGUUUCUGGCUGGGGCCAAAGCUACAGCAGAUUGUGGCUGGGGAGAAGACUUGGUCUUAAAGGGGAGAGAUGGGUGCACACCCAAAAGCAUUUGUUUUCUGCCUUCCGAAGACUUCUGGACCGACAAGCCCAGGGAAGACCAGAAAGUAUGUAGCGCACAGCCAAGUGAUGAAGA